AGUUUUUAAUUGAUGUAGUAUUAUUGAAUAUAUAGUCUAUAUUCAUGUUUUCCCCAAUUGUUCCAAUAAUGGUUCUUUUUAGCCUUUUUUUUUUUUUUUUAAACAAAAAAUCUAGGAUCCAGUCGAGGUUCAUUCACUUCCUUUAAUUGCCGUAAGAGUAGCCCACCCUUCCUCUGCCUUCUUUUGACUUUGCUAACACUGAUAUUUUUUUAAAAACCAAGCCAUCCAUGGCCAGGCACAGUGGCUCAUGUCUGUAACCCCAGCACUUUGGGAGGCCAAGGCAAGUGGAUUGCUUGAGCCUAGGAGUUCGAGACCAGCCUGGACAACAUGAUGAAACCCUGUCUGUAUAAAAAAUAGCUGGGCAUGGUGGCAUGUGCCUGGAGUCCCAGCUACUCAGGAAACUGAGGUGGGAGAAUGGCUUGAGCCCUGCCUGCAGUGAACCGAGAUCAGGCCACUGCACUCCAGCCUGGGCAACAGAGCCAAACCCUGUCUCAAAAAAAAAAAAAGACCAGGCCAGUUUUCUUGUAGAAUGUCUCAUAGUCCAGACUUACCUGAUUUUUCCUUAUGGUUGUCUUCUGGUUUAACACAUUUGACAGGAAAACUAACAAAGCAAAUGUAGCUUUUGUAUUUCGUCACAUCCAAAGGCACAUAAUAUCAAUUGGUCCAACUAUUAAUGAUGCUCAGUUCAAUCACUUAGUAUUGAUAAGGUGAUAUACACCAUAUUUUUCCAUUGCAAAGAUAUCUUUUUUCUUUGUUAUUUAGGAAAAAUAGUGGGGGUUGGCAAGUGACAUUGGUGCAACAAAUGGGGAGAAAUGGCAGGGGAGAAGGAGGUGAUACUUUGAGACAUUGUGUAUAUCAUUCUUAAACAGCCUUUCUUCUAAUGGUUUUAUCAUCCAUGAUCUUUGCCUGACUCAACUGGUGGCAACAAAAUGGUGAUUGCCUAAUUUUGCCCUUUCGUCUACUUGUACUAGCUGGCUGGCUUCUAUUAAAAAAAGAGCUUUCCUCCUUUUACUUUUUUUUUUUUUUUUUAAGUAUUACCAUGGACUCUGAGAUAGUCUUUUUAUUCAAUAUGCUAUAGUCCAUUAUCAUUAUUCUUUUUGAUGUUCACCUUUUCCCAUGGUUGACUAAUGAAAACUGCUUUAGGCCAGCUUCUCUAUAAUCUUGACAUGUGGCCAUCAUUCUUUGAGCAAGUCUCACCUUACACAUUUUUGCCCUAACUUUGAAUCAACCAUUUCUCCAGAGUCCUGAUUCCUUUUAGGAAGAGAAACCAAGAUCUGGACAGUAUGUUCAUUGCUUCUACUUCAGUGGGCAAGCUAGGUAAUAAUAUAUAUUCUUUAUGAGUUUAUACAGAUGCUUCCCGUUACGAUCCAGUACCACGGGCUUCUUCCAUUCCAUUUCCUCUUCUGUGUUUUUUAUCUCCCUCUACUACCCUGACAACUCUGGUUCCCACCAUCAGUAUAUGUACUCACUUGCUCUCUACUAGAGCAUAGCAGUCCCCAACCUUUUUGGCAUCAGGGACUAGUUUCGUGGAAGAUGAUUUUGCCAUGGACCUGGGGCGGGGGAGGGAGGAUGGUUUCAAGAUGAAACUGUUCCACCUCAGAUCAUCAGGCAUUUGUUAGAUUCUCAUAAGGAACGCACAACCUAGAUCUCUUGCAUCCACAGCUGCCCACCUCUUGGUACAUACACGUCCUGUAGUACAUACAAAUAGUUUUGGAAUUACACCAGUACCACUAUGAACAACACGUCUCAGUUUGAGAUUUCUUUGCACUUCAUUUUGUCCUUAGUAUAUAUCUCAGUAAGGGUAUAUAGACAGAAUACUGUAUUCAGAAGUUAAUUUCUUUUUUAUUAUCUGUGUGAUUAUCAAUUUGAUACACAACUAGGUUCAUUUGUUUUUGUUUGACUUCGGUUUUGAGGUGUACUUCUGUUUCCAGAAUUGGUUCCUUCCGGUGGGUUCUUGGUCUCACUGACUUCAAGAAUGAAGCCGCAGACCCUCGUGUAUUGGAUGAACGAAUAUACCUCAUCCAUUGGAAUUGGAGUUUUUCAUUCAGGAAUUGAAGUCUAUGGCAGAGAAUUUGCUUAUGGUGGCCAUCCUUACCCCUUUUCUGGAAUAUUUGAAAUUUCCCCAGGAAAUGCUUCUGAACUAGGAGAAACAUUUAAAUUUAAAGAAGCUGUUGUUUUAGGGAGCACGGACUUCCUAGAAGAUGAUAUAGAAAAAAUUGUAGAAGAACUGGGAAAAGAAUACAAAGGCAAUGCUUAUCAUUUAAUGCAUAAAAACUGCAAUCAUUUUUCUUCAGCUUUAUCAGAGAUUCUUUGUGGGAAAGAGAUUCCUCGCUGGAUCAAUCGACUUGCCUACUUCAGCUCCUGUAUACCCUUUCUACAGAGUUGCCUCCCGAAGGAGUGGCUCACGCCCGCAGCCCUGCAGUCUAGUGUCAGCCAAGAACUCCAGGAUGAACUGGAGGAAGCAGAGGAUGCUGCCGCAUCCGCUUCCGUGGCAAGCACUGCAGCAGGCUCCAGACCCGGGCGCCACACUAAACUAUAAAUGUCUCCAAAGUCACACAUUCAGAACUGUCUCUGGCAGUCGAAUAUCACUAGAGAAAAGUAAACAGAGAAGCAUCCUUUAGAUAUUUUGUAUGCAAAGAUGGCUCUCCCCCAAAUCCCAGUUUUUCAGCUCAGGAUUAUAUUUGUAAUCAAAAAAAAAAAAUCACUUGGCGCAGGAGGGAGAACUUUGUAAGAAGCUGCCCUCUGUUUUUUUUAUCCACUCGUAAAUCUGGAUUUAUUUCUUCUGUUUUAUACAAGCUCUGUUAAGUUAUGUUUACAGUAUCUUGUAUCGCUGUUUACAAAUCUUGCAUGGACUCCUGCCACAGUGAAAGAAGAAAAUCUUCAUGUCUUCAAAAAUUAGGCAGGUAAUCUUUGUAUACUUCUGACAAUUGCCAGAUCUAUGGCAUAAAUAGGCACACAAAAAGGUACUUAAACAGUUAUAGUCACCAUCACCUGCUUCAGAAUGGUCUUUUAGAUUUGUGUUUGUUUUGUUAAAGUUGUUGGCACCAGGAUGCAGAGAAUCAGACUGGCCUGAGGUGAAGGAGCACACAGCCCUGAGGGCUUGGAACCCUGGGUCCAGUUCCUCUUCACACCCCCUUCCACUCUGAGUAGCACAUCUCCCCAGGUGCCCAUGGAACACCUGCUUUCAUCCCAAAUAUCCGUCCACCUAGGCGGGGUGGUAUGUUCUUACGUCUCUCUGACUUUGAUGCCACUCAUUCUAUAGUUUAGCUGGUUUUCGUUCAAGAUAUUCUUGGUAGUAACUGACAAGUAUGUUGCACAUGUAUUGGGGGAGGCGCUUCAUUUUUAUUUUAAUACACAUGUAUUUCCUCCUUGCACAGGAUUUUGAUGGUGUGGGAAUAUCCUAAGUGGUAGCCUUCCAAGUAGCAGUGAGUUGACAUUCAGCUGCUUUUAACUAUUCAGGCUACCUUUUAUACUAAACCUUGAAAACUAGAAUCUAAUGUCUACCCCAAAAAAGUAGUUCUUUGAUAUUUUAUACUUUUUAUGUACCAUGUCAGAAAGAGUAUGUUGGCGUUUGUCAUGGGACUCAUUUCACAUAAUAGAAUGCCUAGUCUCAUUGACCAAUCGUUAAAAAAUCAUAUUUGUGUGUCUUAAGAUUCAUAUUUAUAUGUUCUCUCAAAUGUAUGUCUCUUACGUAACAUACUCUAAGAAUGAAACUGUCACCACAGGUAAAUCCUUGUUAGCAAGGAAUCUGUCUGCUCCAGUCUACUCCUAGUUUGAUCCUUGGAUGUAAGAACCAAGUCAUUACAUGUCAAAUUCAAUUUUUCUGCCUUAAGAAUGAAUGUCCUUCAUAAAAUAUUGGAUGCAGUGUAACACUAUCCAAGGCAGUGACUUCAGCUUUAUAUACAUAUAAAAUAUAGUUAGUUUUAAAAUUAUUGACAUUUAUUUAAACUUUUAGAUUGGAUUGUUUGCUAUUGCUCUGUGUGAGGAUACAUAAUCUUUCAGUAAACUGUAUUUUUAACUUUUCCAUAAGCUGAUUUUGGUUCAUUUUAUCAACGUAAGCACACCCUGUUCAUAGGGAAAAUAAACCUUGGGUUAUAAGCAUUAGCCUGAGGACAAUGAAGCCACUUAACCUAAUUUAUGCUUUCGACUGUUCUGUUUCCAGAGAGGAAAGCCUUUACAAAUUACUCUCAGUUCUUUAGGGGCAGAAGGCUUGUUUCAAGAGGUUUGACAGAAGAAAGGAAUAUAUGAACUUAAUGAGAUGUCGACUUGGUUCAGGUCUAAAAAUGAGGGCAAAACACUAAGGCUCUAGCAGUGACUUGUUCACUAAAAAGAGAGAGUCCUGUCCCCAGACGGUUAGUACAAAGCCUUGGAUACAGUUUGCUUGUAAUAUUUUUAAUAAUGUGAGGAGUACAGUGUUUUCUAAUUCAUUCAAGUAUAUAUGAUUUAAACCUGGGCUACUGACACACACACAGUAGCCAUUAGUUAGACUCUUCUUAGUGAAUAUCAGGAACAUCCCAUCUGUGCUUAACCAGAAUCCAGCAAGUCAGCACACAAGUGAUUUUAUUGUUAUUUUGUUGUAUUUACUUGCAUUUGUUGUAUUUACUUUCAUCUGCAGCAUUUGGAGUUUAAAAAUAAUGUAAAGGGUUCUAGUAGAAAUAGUGUCCUAAGGCCAAUUACCUACCAUACUAACAAUCAGCAGAUAAAAUUCUGGACGUGAGAUUCCUUAUAAUCUAAUUAUACCUGAGGUUGAGCAAGAAAUGUCUUCCUUUAGAAAAUCUCAUUCAAGUCAGGUUCUUCUCUACAGUUCAAAAUUGAGAAUGGAUUUAAUUAACUAGCAUUUAGCCAGCUUUUUCUUGCCCUUGGAGAAAAAGAAUCAUUCUCAACCUGAUAAUCUGUUAAGAAAAAUCCCAUAUGAACAAUCUGGUCAUUAACAUACAUAUGAUACGGAGUCUCUUUGUUGUCACCAAGUGAACAUACUUCUCAUGGUGGGUUGGACAGUAAUACAUGUUAGAGGGUCAGAAGCUUCUGGUUUCUGCUGUUUGCUUUAAAUACCCUUGGGGUUUUUUUUUAAACCCUUACAAGGGGAGCAUCAGCUUUGGAAAGUGUGACUCUGUAGGAGUGUAGAAGGCAGUGGUGUAUGAUCUUAGCCUCGUCCUGAUGCCUGAAUCCAGCCAGCUGUUGCUCUGACCCACAGCAAUAGAGCAAGUUACCCAUCACCAGCAUUUGUACAGAGCAGGGAAUUCUGGUUUUAGUCCAUUGGUAGCAUUGUGUGUAUGAGGAGAUUCAACACCACAGACAGCUGCAGGACUCGAUAUCCAUGGCUUCUUUCCAUCACAAAACGGGUAGAAACACAUUCACUGCUUCAGGGUUCUAAUCUGUGUGUCUCCUUAUGACUCCAUUUCUGUAAGCUACUCUGUAACUUUGAUAUAUGCUGUAUUUUCUUUCUUUAAAAGAUUUAGAUGUUUUUUCAGCAAGCUAGCCAUACAACCAUUGUAUCUCUUUCUCUUCAGUAUGGUUUAGAGCCCAGAUCAGUUAGUAGGCUUUCGUUGUCUUCUCUUUCAAUACAUGUACAUCUUUACUGUUUGAAAAGUGUUACAGCUGUCAAAGAAUCUUCAUGGACCUGAAGAUAAUUUCUUGUGAAGUUGAAUGCAAGUGUACUGUCAUUCAUAGUGUUUAUAUCAAAAUACCAGGAAUCUUCACUUUUGCUACCUUGAUAUAGCAUUGGGCUAUCAUGUUACAACAUUGAAAUACAUUGAUUUAUUAAAAAAUACUUUUAUAAGAAA